ACACAGAGACAGAGUAGCCCAUAGGCCAAACCACUCUACCAAGGACAGCCCAAGAACUGGUCUAGCCUGGCAGCCUUUUCCCUCGGGUAGUAGAGGCUGCCCCUCUGACAGGGAGUUUGUGGUCAGCGAGUGGGCCCUUGGGGGUCUUGGGCUGUCACAGGGACUCCAGAAAGCCAUGCAGAGCCUUGUGCCAUGAAGGACUUCUCAGAUGUCAUCCUCUGCAUGGAGGCAACAGAAUCGAGCAAGACCGAGUUCUGCAAUCCUGCCUUCGAGCCUGAGUCUGGGCCACCCUGCCCUCCCCCAGUUUUCCCAGAGGAUGCCAGCUACAGCGUCCCAGCUCCCUGGCAUGGUCGGCGUCCUCGAGGGCUACGGCCAGACUGCCGCUUCUCCUGGCUCUGUGUCCUCCUGCUCUCCAGCCUGCUCCUCCUGCUGCUUGGGCUGCUGGUGGCCAUCAUCCUGGCCCAGCUGCAGGCUGCACCCCCAUCUGGGGCGUCCCAUAGCCCACUGCCUGCCGGAGGCCUUACCACGACCACCACCACCCCCACCAUCACCACCUCUCAGGCAGCUGGGACCCCUAAAGGGCAGCAGGAGUCAGGCGUGAGCCCCUCCCCACAGUCCACCUGUGGAGGCCUCCUCUCUGGCCCAAGGGGCUUCUUCAGCAGCCCUAACUACCCAGACCCUUACCCCCCCAACACCCACUGCGUGUGGCAUAUCCAGGUGGCCACAGACCAUGCAAUACAGCUCAAGAUCGAAGCCCUCAGCAUAGAGAGUGUGGCCUCUUGCCUUUUUGAUCGCUUGGAACUCUCCCCUGAGCCUGAAGGCCCCCUCCUCAGGGUUUGUGGAAGGGUGCCUCCCCCCACGCUCAACACCAAUGCCAGCCACCUCCUGGUGGUCUUCGUCUCUGACAGCAGUGUGGAAGGAUUUGGUUUCCAUGCCUGGUACCAGGCUAUGGCCCCUGGGCGCGGGAGCUGUGCCCAUGAUGAGUUCCGCUGUGACCAGCUCAUCUGCCUGCUACCUGACUCAGUGUGUGAUGGUUUUGCCAACUGUGCUGACGGCAGUGAUGAGACCAAUUGCAGUGCCAAGUUCUCGGGGUGUGGGGGGAAUCUGACUGGCCUCCAGGGCACUUUCUCUACUCCCAGCUACCUGCAGCAGUACCCUCACCAACUGCUCUGCACCUGGCAUAUCUCGGUGCCUGCCGGACACAGCAUAGAACUACAGUUCCACAACUUCAGCCUGGAGGCUCAGGACGAGUGCAAGUUUGACUACGUGGAGGUGUAUGAGACCAGCAGCUCAGGGGCCUUCAGCCUCCUGGGCAGGUUCUGUGGAGCAGAGCCACCCCCCCACCUCGUCUCCUCGCACCAUGAGCUGGCUGUGCUGUUUAGGACAGAUCAUGGCAUCAGCAGUGGAGGCUUCUCAGCCACCUACCUGGCCUUCAAUGCCACGGAGAACCCCUGUGGGCCCAGUGAGCUCUCCUGCCAGGCAGGAGGGUGUAAGGGUGUGCAGUGGAUGUGUGACAUGUGGAGAGACUGCACCGAUGGCAGCGAUGACAACUGCAGCGGCCCCUUGUUCCCACCCCCAGAGCUGGCCUGUGAGCCUGUCCAGGUGGAGAUGUGCCUCGGUCUGAGCUACAACACCACAGCCUUCCCUAACAUCUGGGUGGGCAUGAUCACCCAGGAGGAGGUGGUAGAGGUCCUCAGCGGUUACAAGAGCCUGACAAGCCUGCCCUGCUACCAGCAUUUCCGGAGGCUCCUGUGUGGGCUGCUUGUGCCCCGUUGCACCCCACUAGGCAGUGUUCUGCCCCCUUGCCGCUCUGUCUGCCAGGAAGCGGAGCACCAGUGCCAGUCUGGCCUGGCACUACUGGGCACCCCCUGGCCCUUCAACUGCAACAGGCUGCCAGAGGCAGCUGACCUGGAAGCUUGUGCCCAGCCCUGACCCUGAAGCCGGCCCCUGCCCUCUUCCUGCCCGUCCUCUUUUGCCGGUCAGGGCUGGCACGCAGGGGAACAAAGGAAGGAGCAUCAGCAGGGUCUCUACCCAUCCUUCUCUGGGGCUCCCAGGGAGGGGGAAGAGAAGUCCUCAGCUGGGGCUCAUGGGACCCUACCACCCUCCCUGCUCCUUCCUGUCCCUUUACCGGUCCCAGGCUGCUGACUGGCCCCACACUGUGCCACCGGACAAUCGAGACCACUUCCCAUCCAGGCCUCUUCCCCUUUCCAUCUGCUUUUUCAGCUUCUCCAUCGCCUGCCUUCUGACCUUUUCCUUGAUUCAACAAAAAUGUACUGAGCAUCUAUUCAUGUGGCAGGCCCCUGUCCUAGGCCCUAGGGAUCCAACUGGCUGUCUGCCUCUAGAACUCUCCACCCUCAUCUCUCUGCGUAUUUCUCCCUGAAAUGGGGUCUGGUCCUUGGUCUCUGCCACUGCCCUGCCUCUCCUCUGGCCCUGGGAACAGGAGGUGCCCUGUGUGUCCGUCUCUCGAAGUUCUGCCUCUCUGUGCCCAGCUCAAGUCUCUCUCCCCCUCCUUUCUCCCCCUAAACUUUGGCCGGCCGCCGGGCGACACCACGAGUUAUUUCCCAGCUAUUUCCCGGUCCGGGAGCUCUUGGCCCCUGAACAACUGGUUUCCUCUUGGAGUCUGGGAGGAGGAAAGCGGAGCCGGCAGGGAGCGAACCAGGACUGGGGUGACGGCAGGGCAGGGGGCGCCUGGCCGGGGAGAAGCGCGGGGGCUGGAGCACCACCAACUGGAGGGUCCGGAGUAGCGAGCGCCCCGAAGGAGGCCAUCGGGGAGCCGGGAGGGGGGACUGCGAGAGGACCCCGGCGUCCGGGCUCCCGGUGCCAGCGCUAUGAGGCCACUCCUCGUCCUGCUGCUCCUGGGCCUGGCGGCCGGCUCGCCCCCACUGGACGACAACAAGAUCCCCAGCCUCUGCCCGGGGCACCCCGGCCUUCCAGGCACGCCGGGCCACCAUGGCAGCCAGGGCUUGCCGGGCCGCGAUGGCCGCGACGGCCGCGACGGCGCGCCCGGGGCUCCGGGAGAGAAAGGCGAGGGCGGGAGGCCGGGACUGCCGGGACCUCGAGGGGACCCCGGGCCGCGAGGAGAGGCGGGACCCGCGGGGCCCACCGGGCCUGCCGGGGAGUGCUCGGUGCCUCCGCGAUCCGCCUUCAGCGCCAAGCGCUCCGAGAGCCGGGUGCCUCCGCCGUCUGACGCACCCUUGCCCUUCGACCGCGUGCUGGUGAACGAGCAGGGACAUUACGACGCCGUCACCGGCAAGUUCACCUGCCAGGUGCCUGGGGUCUACUACUUCGCCGUCCAUGCCACCGUCUACCGGGCCAGCCUGCAGUUUGAUCUGGUGAAGAAUGGCGAAUCCAUUGCCUCUUUCUUCCAGUUUUUCGGGGGGUGGCCCAAGCCAGCCUCGCUCUCGGGGGGGGCCAUGGUGAGGCUGGAGCCUGAGGACCAAGUGUGGGUGCAGGUGGGUGUGGGUGACUACAUUGGCAUCUAUGCCAGCAUCAAGACAGACAGCACCUUCUCCGGAUUUCUGGUGUACUCCGACUGGCACAGCUCCCCAGUCUUUGCUUAGUGCCCACUGCAAAGUGAGCUCAUGCUCUCACUCCUAGAAGGAGGGUGUGAGGCUGACAACCAGGUCAUCCAGGAGGGCUGGCCCCCCUGGAAUAUUGUGAAUGACUAGGGAGGUGGGGUAGAGCACUCUCCGUCCUGCUGCUGGCAAGGAAUGGGAACAGUGGCUGUCUGCGAUCAGGUCUGGCAGCAUGGGGCAGUGGCUGGAUUUCUGCCCAAGACCAGAGGAGUGUGCUGUGCUGGCAAGUGUAAGUCCCCCAGUUGCUCUGGUCCAGGAGCCCACGGUGGGGUGCUCUCUUCCUGGUCCUCUGCUUCUCUGGAUCCUCCCCACCCCCUCCUGCUCCUGGGGCCGGCCCUUUUCUCAGAGAUCACUCAAUAAACCUAAGAACCCUC